ACACUCGUCUCCGUUUCGGCCUCUGCAGGGUGUAAGCUGCUAAAGAAGCUUCAACCUUAAGGGGGCCUCAGGGAGAGAGUUGUGCUCCUGCCGCCGAGAGCUCCACCUUCGUGGCUCUGGGUCCGGGGCCCCGGCCUGUGGCGGCGAGCGGCGGCCGCUGGAGACGAGCGGCGGCGGCAGGCGGCCAGCCCGGGUCUGCCUCGCUCCGUGCAGGGCCGGGAGAGGGAUCCGCCAUAUUGGAGCUGGGGCCGAAGGUGCCUUGGAGCCGCGGCGCGAGGCGGGUGGAGGUGGCGGCCCUGGCCUGGAUCGGGAAGGAGUCGGCUCUGCCCUGGCCCGCAAGGCUGGGGAGCUAAUGAGCCUCUCUGGCUAGUCUCCUCCCCGUCCACUCCCUCCACUUUCUGCCGCCGGGACCCGGCUGGGAGCCGGCUGUGGCAGUGGCAGUGGCAGUGGCAGCGACAGGAUGUUCUCCAAGAAGCCGCACGGGGACGUGAAGAAGUCCACCCAGAAGGUGCUAGACACCAAGAAGGACGCACUGACUCGCCUCAAGCACCUGCGCAUCGUCAUCGAGAAUGCAGAAUCUAUUGAUCUUAAACAGUUUUUCGACCAACAUUUUUCACAUAUAUACUAUGUGUUCUUUGAAAAUUUUGUGACUAUUGAAGCUAGUCUUAAACAGAAAGGUCACAAGUCUCAAAGAGAGGAAUUGGAUGCUAUACUUUUUAUUUUUGAGAAAAUUUUACAACUUCUUCCAGAAAGAAUUCAUCAGCGAUGGCAGUUUCAUAGUAUUGGAUUGAUUUUAAAGAAGCUACUUCACACAGGAAACUCCUUAAAGAUUAGGCGGGAAGGUGUUCGUCUUUUCUUACUAUGGUUGCAAGCUCUUCAGAAUAACUGUAGCAAAGAACAGCUCUGGAUGUUUUCAUGCUUAAUCCCUGGAUUUUCAGCACCACAGUCUGAACAUGGACCUCGAACUUUAGAUAAUCUCAUUAAUCCUCCACUCAACCUUCAAGAAACUCAAGUCACUAUAGAAGAAAUCACUCCUCUUGUCCCCCCACAAUCAGGAGAUAAAGGGCAAGAAGAUCUCACAAGCUAUUUUCUUGAAGCACUUCUAAAAUACAUAGUCAUUCAGGUAAAAAGUUUAGAAUGGAAGAACAAAGAAAACCAAGAAAGGGGAUUUUCAUUUUUGUUUUCACAUUUUAAGAAAUAUUACUUGCCUUAUAUUUUUCCAAACAUCUGUAAGGAAAACAGUUUAUAUCAUCCUAUACUUGACAUCCCGCAGAUGAGACCAAAGCCACAUUAUGUCGUGAUAAAGAAAGAUGCUGAAACCAAUGAAGCAAUCUAUUGUACAAAGGAGCCUUUCAUUAAGGCUCGUGUUAUUGUCAUUCGUUGGCUGGUUUCUUUCUGGCUGGAGCCAAAACCACAUACAGGACCUCAUAUUCCUGGGAUGGAAGGUGAAGUCUUGCCAAAGAAUAUUCAGAGAGCAGCUGCUAGUUUAGUAUCCAGAGAAGAAAGCAAAAAUGAUAAUGCUGAUAAAACAGACAGAACUACAGAACCCGAACAGUCUCAUUCCAAUACAAGCACUCUCACGGAGCGAGAACCUAGCUCAUCUAGUCUCUGUAGUAUUGAUGAAGAACAUCUCACAGACAUUGAAAUAGUUCGCAGAGUUUUUUCUUCUAAAAGGAGUAAUGUAAACUUUGUGACAGAGAUAUUUCGUCAGGCAUUUUUAUUACCAAUUUGUGAAGCAGCAGCUAUGAGAAAAGUGGUAAAAGUAUAUCAAGAAUGGAUCCAACAAGAGGAAAAACCUUUGUUCAUGCAAGAGCCUGAAGAAAUUGUGAUCACUUCUUCAGACCUCCCUUGCAUUGAAAAUGUCACAGACCAUGAUAUUUCAAUGGAAGAAGGAGAAAAAAGAGAAGAGGAAAAUGGGACCAAUACUGCUGAUCAUGUUCGAAAUUCCAGUUGGGCAAAAAACGGCUCCUACCAAGGUGCUCUUCAUAACGCCUCUGAAGAAGCCACAGAACAAAACAUACGAGCUGGUACCCAGGCAGUUUUGCAGGUGUUUAUUAUAAACUCAUCAAAUAUAUUUCUUCUUGAACCUGCAAAUGAAAUAAAAAAUCUUCUGGAUGAACACACAGAUAUGUGUAAACGCAUUCUUAACAUUUAUCGGUACAUGGUUGUACAAGUAUCAAUGGACAAAAAGACUUGGGAACAGAUGCUGCUUGUGUUGCUCAGAGUCACGGAAUCUGUACUGAAGAUGCCAUCACAAGCUUUUCUACAGUUCCAAGGGAAAAAAAAUAUGACCUUGGCAGGUCGACUUGCAGGACCACUUUUCCAGACCCUUAUAGUUGCCUGGAUCAAAGCAAACCUAAAUGUGUACAUCUCCCGAGAACUUUGGGAUGACUUACUGUCAGUAUUGUCAUCGCUGACCUAUUGGGAAGAGUUGGCCACUGAGUGGUCACUGACUAUGGAGACAUUAACUAAAGUUUUAGCUAGGAAUUUAUAUAGUUUGGAUCUCAGUGAUUUACCAUUGGAUAAGCUGAGUGAACAGAAACAAAAAAAGCACAAAGGGAAAGGAGUUGGACAUGAAUUUCAGAAAGUUUCAGUUGACAAGUCAUUUUCUAGAGGAUGGAGUCGUGAUCAGCCUGGCCAAGCCCCAAUGAGACAGAGGAGUGCAACAACCACUGGUUCUCCAGGAACCGAAAAGGCGAGGAGUAUAGUACGGCAAAAAACUGUCGCCAUGAGAAGCCGAUCCAUUGGUGAAUGUGCUCUGCCAUCGGCCUAUAUACGCAGUGCUAAAAGUGCUCCUGUUCUGAUCCAUACUUCCAAACCCUUCUUGCCUGAUAUUGUUCUCACUCCCCUUUCUGAUGAGCUUUCAGAUAUUGAUGAUGCUCAAAUACUUCCCCGCUCAACUAGAGUCAGACAUUUUUCACAAAGUGAAGAAACUGGAAAUGAAGUUUUUGGUGCUUUGAAUGAGGAGCAGCCAUUGCCUCGAAGUAGCAGCACUUCUGACAUCUUGGAACCAUUCACUGUUGAACGAGCCAAAGGUGCAGUUCCUGUCAUUGACAGUUCAUCCCGUCAUGCACCAAGCUUGCAGAGUUCCACAGAGGCUUCUUCAAUAACUAGAUCCACUGAAAGCCACAUCACUGAUACUCAUAGUAGAGAGUCUUCUCUGGAAGUUGGUGAUAGCAUAUAUGACCAUCUUUGUCAUUUAAUAGGUCCAGUAGAACUUGCAGAUUCAGCUUUUGAACAAAUCCAGUACAUUGACCUUGAAGGAGAUGAUGAUCUUCUUUCCACCCUGAAAGAAUAUUUUAAGGAAAACCAGGAAAAUCAUAGUAAAAAUGAGACAGGGAAAGACCCAGCUUCUCAGGAAGUGACUAUUGCAGUAAAUAGGGGUGAAAGAUUAUCCUUAGAUAAAUUAGAAUGCACAGAUCAGGAAACUGAAUCAGAAAAUAUCACCUCUUUUGUUGGGACUCCUGAAAACCUACAGUUUCAGAAAGAACCAAACUCAGCUGUCUUCAUGAGUAAUAUCGCACCUAACCAGUCAGACAGUUUUUUUAGAACACAAACUUCUGAAAAAUCUAAGCAACUAAACACUGAUAAACAGCCAUCAGAGCCUAGUUUAGAUAGCCCUUGUGAUAAAGAAAAAAGGAAACAUCUGUACAGACAAGCAGCCACAGAAUUAGAUGCUUGUGUUGAUGUAACACUAGUUGAAAAGCUUAAGAGUGUGCAAAUUAAUGAAAAAAUCACUGUCCCACAUGUUAUGCGUGCCAAGAAAGCAACACUAAAAGCACCUGUUAACCGCAGAAUGCCUCAUGUUACAAGUACUAGCAAACUUUCUCCAACUAAAAGGAGCUUGUCUGAAACAGUAACUCAUAGAGCCAAAAUCAUGAAAAUUGCUACUAAAAAACGAAAUAGUGUUCAUGUUACUUUUAGGCCAUCCACUGAGUCCGUUCAGUUUUAUAAUCCUCUGGAAAACAAAGAGGCUCCAUGGAAGAUGAGACUGCGGAAGCUCGGUGGCUUUAGUAGUGGUAGCAGCAAUAGCAGCACUAGCAACACCCAUACCAGCACAAAUAGUGCUACAGAGCUAGUAAAACCUGGUGUGUACAGACCUCUAGAUACACUUGGUACUGCAUCAGUAAGCAGCAAAACAGUGAAGGAAUCCACAGAGAUUCCCACCACCAUAUUACAAAAAGAAGGAAUUGCAAGUAGUCAAUUAGGUAGUCGUAGUACUCUUAGGUCAUCAAGUCAUGAGGCAGGACUACAGCAGGGCUCCCUGGGUGGCGUUUAUAAAACUGUUGUACAUGCUCUUUCGAAGCCGAAGGCAAAUGUUUCCCCACAGAGGCAGAACAGAAUGCCACCAGAGGCUCCACUGAGGGAUCUGUACAGUCAUGUAAUGGGCUAUUUUGGAAGGAAAGCUGCAGUCAAUAAAGAGGACAUGAGCCAAAAACUGCCUCCUCUUAAUAGUGAUAUUGGCGGCAGCAGUGCUAAUGUUCCUGAUCUGAUGGAUGAGUUUAUAGCAGAACGACUUCGAAGUGGUAAUGCCUCGACUAUGACAAGAAGAGGAAGUAGUCCAGGCAGCCUGGAAAUUCCCAAAGACCUCCCUGAUAUUCUAAACAAGCAGAACCAGAUGCGCCCUAUUGAUGACCCAGGUGUGCCCUCAGAAUGGACUUCUCCUGCCAGUGCAGGGAGCAGUGAUCUUAUCAGCUCAGAUAGUCAUUCGGAUUCUUUCAGCGCUUUCCAAUAUGAUGGCCGAAAAUUUGACAAUUUUGGCUUUGGAACCGACACUGGGGUUACGUCCUCUGCUGAUGUGGAUUCAGGUUCUGGCCAUCAUCAGAGUGCUGAAGAGCAGGAAGUGGCUAGUCUAACUACUCUUCAUAUAGAUUCUGAAACAAGCAGUCUUAAUCAGCAAGCUUUCUCUGCUGAAGUUGCAACUAUUACUGGUUCAGAAAGUGCUUCCCCAGUCCACUCACCUCUGGGCUCCAGGUCACAGACUCCUUCCCCUUCUACAUUGAAUAUAGAUCACAUGGAACAGAAGGAUCUGCAGCUCGACGAGAAGCUCCACCACUCUGUUCUUCAGACACCAGAUGAUCUAGAAAUUAGUGAAUUUCCAUCAGAAUGUUGUAGUGUGAUGGCAGGAGGUACUCUGACUGGAUGGCAUGCUGAUGUUGCUACUGUAAUGUGGCGAAGAAUGCUAGGCAUUUUGGGAGAUGUAAAUUCAAUCAUGGAUCCUGAAAUACAUGCUCAAGUUUUUGAUUACCUCUGUGAACUUUGGCAGAAUCUAGCUAAGAUUAGAGAUAACCUUGGCAUUUCAACUGAUAACCUGACCUCCCCUUCUCCACCAGUUUUAAUUCCUCCACUGAGAAUUCUUACACCUUGGCUUUUUAAGGCAACCAUGUUGACUGAUAAAUAUAAACAAGGUAAAUUACAUGCAUAUAAACUUAUUUGUAAUACAAUGAAAAGAAGACAAGAUGUUUCUCCAAAUAGAGAUUUUCUAACACAUUUCUACAAUAUAAUGCAUUGUGGAUUACUUCAUAUUGACCAGGAUAUUGUCAAUACAAUCAUCAAACACUGCUCACCUCAAUUUUUUUCACUUGGUUUGCCUGGUGCCACAAUGCUUAUUAUGGAUUUUAUUGUAGCAGCUGGUAGAGUGGCUUCUUCAGCUUUUCUCAAUGCACCAAGAGUAGAAGCACAAGUUCUUCUGGGAUCUUUGGUUUGCUUUCCCAACUUAUAUUGUGAACUGCCUUCUCUUCAUCCCAACAUUCCUGAUGUUGCUGUGUCUCAGUUUACAGAUGUUAAGGAACUUAUAAUCAAAACUGUAUUAAGCUCGGCAAGAGAUGAGCCCUCUGGUCCUGCACGAUGUGUAGCACUUUGUAGUUUAGGUAUUUGGAUUUGUGAAGAACUAGUCCAUGAGUCUCAUCAUCCUCAAAUUAAGGAAGCUCUGAAUGUGAUUUGUGUUUCCUUAAAGUUUACUAAUAAAACAGUAGCCCACGUAGCUUGUAACAUGCUUCACAUGCUGGUUCAUUAUGUACCUAGACUUCAGAUUUACCAGCCUGAUUCUCCCUUGAAAAUUAUUCAAAUCCUAAUAGCUACCAUCACCCAUCUUUUACCAAGUACAGAGGCUUCAUCUUAUGAAAUGGACAAGAGGUUGGUAGUAUCUUUACUUCUCUGCCUUCUGGACUGGAUCAUGGCCUUACCUCUAAAGACACUGCUCCAACCAUUUCAUGCUACGGGAGCAGAAAGCGAUAAAACAGAAAAAUCUGUUCUCAAUUGCAUUUAUAAGGUUUUACAUGGGUGUGUUUAUGGAGCUCAGUGUUUUAGCAAUCCAAGGUAUUUUCCCAUGAGCCUCUCUGAUUUGGCAUCUGUAGAUUAUGAUCCUUUUAUGCAUUUGGAAAGUCUGAAAGAGCCUGAGCCUCUGCACUCUCCUGACUCAGAACGAUCUUCUAAACUCCAGCCAGUAACAGAAGUGAAAACUCAAAUGCAGCAUGGAUUAAUCUCUAUAGCAGCCCGCACUGUUAUUACACAUCUGGUAAAUCACCUGGGCCAUUAUCCAAUGAGCGGUGGUCCUGCUAUGCUAACAAGUCAGGUGUGUGAAAAUCACGACAAUCAUUACAGUGAAAGUACUGAACUUUCUCCUGAACUCUUUGAGAGUCCAAAUAUCCAGUUCUUUGUGUUAAAUAAUACAACCUUAGUGUCCUGUAUCCAGAUCAGAUCAGAAGAGAAUAUGCCUGGAGGAGGUUUAUCUGCUGGCCUUGCAUCAGCCAAUUCAAAUGUCAGAAUCAUAGUACGUGAUCUCUCUGGAAAAUAUUCAUGGGAUUCUGCUAUACUGUAUGGCCCACCUCCUGUAAGUGGCUUGUCAGAACCUACAUCUUUCAUGCUUUCAUUGUCUCACCAAGAGAAGCCAGAAGAGCCUCCGACAUCUAAUGAAUGCUUAGAAGAUAUAACCGUAAAAGAUGGACUUUCUCUCCAGUUUAAAAGAUUUAGAGAAACUGUACCAACUUGGGAUACAAUAAGAGAUGAAGAAGAUGUUCUUGAUGAGCUCUUGCAGUAUUUGGGUGUUACUAGUCCUGAAUGCUUACAGAGAACUGGAAUCUCACUUAAUAUUCCUGCUCCACAACCUGUGUGCAUUUCUGAAAAACAAGAAAAUGAUGUUAUUAAUGCUAUCCUUAAGCAACAUACAGAAGAAAAAGAAUUUGUUGAGAAGCACUUUAAUGACUUAAACAUGAAAGCUGUGGAACAAGAUGAACCAAUACCUCAAAAACCUCAGUCAGCAUUUUAUUAUUGCAGAUUGCUUCUUAGUAUAUUGGGAAUGAAUUCCUGGGACAAACGGAGGAGCUUUCAUCUCCUGAAGAAAAAUGAAAAGCUACUUAGAGAACUUAGGAACUUGGAUUCAAGGCAGUGCCGAGAGACACACAAGAUUGCAGUAUUUUAUGUUGCUGAAGGACAAGAAGACAAACACUCCAUUCUCACCAAUACAGGAGGAAGUCAAGCAUAUGAAGAUUUUGUAGCUGGUCUUGGUUGGGAGGUAAAUCUUACAAACCAUUGUGGUUUUAUGGGAGGACUACAAAAAAACAAAAGCACUGGAUUGACCACUCCAUAUUUUGCUACCUCUACAGUAGAGGUAAUAUUUCACGUGUCAACAAGAAUGCCUUCUGAUUCUGAUGAUUCUUUGACCAAAAAAUUGAGACAUUGGGGAAAUUCUGUUAUUAUUGCUUCAAAUAUUGCUUCUGUUCCUUUUUCUCUUUCUUCUUCUUUUGGAGUUCCCAUUACAUGUAUUUACAUCUUUCAUGGUAGUCCCACAGUUUUUGCAUAUUCUGUUUGAAUAUAAAUCUUUUUUCUCUUUGCUUUUCUGUUUUGGAGGUUUCUAUUGAGAUAUCCUGAAGCUCAGAGAUUCUUUCCUCAGCUGUGUCUUGUCUGUGAAUGAGCCUAUCAAAGACAUUUUAAAAUUUCUGUUCCAGUGUUUUUUUAACUCUAGCAUUUUUUCUUGAUUAUUUUUUCCUAGAAUUUCCAUCUCUCUACAUACAUUGUCCAUCUGUUCUUAAAUGUUGUCUACUUUUUCCAUUAGAGCCCCAUAGCAUGUUAACCAUAGUUGUUUUAAAUUCCUGGUCUGAUAAUUCUAGCAUCUCUGCCACAUCUGACUCUGGUGCUUAUUCUGUUCUGAUGCUUGUUCAGUCUCUUUAGACUAUGUUUUUUGUCUUGUAAUUUUUUGUUGAAAUCUGAACAUAUGCUCAGUAAAAGGAACUCUGGUAAAUAGGCCUUUAGUGGUAUGGUGGUAAGGUGUGGGGGAAGGGGAGGCACUCCAUUGUCCCAUCAUUAGGUUUCAGUAUUUUGCUGAGCCUGUGGCCCUGGAUUGUGAACUUCACUAGUGUUUUUCAGUCUCUUCCCUUAGGUGGGACAGUAUGACCUUCCAAGGAGCCAGAGUUGGCUAUUUUUCUUCUCCCAGGUAGAUUAGGCUUUGGUAAAAUAGUUUCUACUGAGGGCAGGCCUUUUAAAGAAGAACAGAAUGUUUUGGUGUGUUUCAAAUAAUUGUUUUUCCCCUCCCCCUCCAUAAAGCAAGAGGAUAUUUUUCUCUAUUAUUCACUGUGAGGACCUGGUAGAGCUCUUGGAAAUAAAACUCACAAAAGUAGGGAAGUUCCCCAUAAGACUGGUUUCUCCUGGAGUUGCUAACUCUUAGACUUGUCCACACUGAGCUUCCAGCAGUUCAAUUUUAGUUCAGGUUUUCCUACACUGGCACUAGAUUCCAUCAGUCAGCUGUAAUUAUCUGUCUCUCUCCAGUGGGACACCAGGAAUGGGGAGGGGAGCAUUUUUCCUGUGACUUCAUGUCUCUGAUGAUGCUAAAAAGAAUUGUUGAUUUUCAGUUUGUUCGGCAUUUUAUUUGUUGUUAGAUCAAAGUGGUGAUUCCAAACCUUUAUAUGCUGCACCAGAAACUGGAAGACCCAGAACUUGUUUUGUUGUUUUUUGUUUUUUGUUUUUGUUCCAGAACUUUUUUAAAUUUUCAAACAGCAACUUUGUACCCAUUAAACAGUAAUUCCCCAUUCCUCCUUCCACUACCCCUGGUAACCUCUAAUCCACUUCCUCUAUGAAUUUGCCAGUUCUAGGAACCUCGAAUAAGUGGAAUCAUAAAAUAUGUGUCCUUUUGUGCCUGUUUUACUUAGCAUGUUUUCAAGAUCCAUUCAUGUUGUAGCAUACAUCAGAAUUUCAUUCCUUUUUAAAGCUGAAUAAUAAUCUGUUGCAAGUAUAUACCUCAUUUUGUUUACCCAUUCAUCUGUGGCUGGAAAUUGGGUUGUUUCCACCUUUUGGUUCUUGUAAACAAUGUUGCAGUGAACAUUGGCAUACAAAUAUCUAUUUGAAUCCCUGUUUUCAAUUUAGCUAUAUAGCUAGGAGUGGAAUUGCUGGGAUCAUAUGGUAAUUGUAUAUGUAGCUUUCUGAGAAAUUGUCAGGAUGUUUUCUACAGCAGCUGCAUCAUUUUAUAUUUCCACCAGGAAUGCUUAAGGGUUGCAAUUUUUCCACAUCUUUGCCAACACUUGUUAUUUUCUGUUUUAAAAAAAUAAUUAUAGCCAUAGUAGUAGGUGUGAAAUGAUAUUUCGUUGUGCUUUUGACUUGUAUUUCCCUUCUAAUGAUAUUGAGCAUCUUUUCAUGUGCUUAUUGCCUAUUUGUAUAUACUCUUUGGAGAAAUGUCUUAUUUUCUCUAGUAGUAAUUUAAAUCAAUUUAAGUAAAAUUUACUUUGUCAGCGUCAAACUAAAUUAAAGCAAUGUUUCAGCUCUAUAUGUAUGAACAAUGUGGUCAUAUACGUCCUGAUACUGCGAUUCUCCAAGAAACAAUAGCAGCUUUUAAGUCCAACAGAAAGGGAAUUUUUAUUUGAUCUCAUAAUUCAGUGUAAUUAGCUUAAACUUUCUUUUCGUAGAAAUUUUUUAAAACCUUAUAAACAUUGAUUUCUCUAUAUACUGAUGUUUCCCGUUUCCCUAUACCUAAUGACUGUUGCCUUAAUCUUUUCCUCAGAGUUCUAGUAUAUAAGAUUUUUCUAAGUAGCAGGCUUAUAUUUUAGUUUUAUUUUAGUAUCACUUUAUUUUUGAUAGGUUAAAUGUUUAAACUUAAUCGUAGAAGCCAGUUGUCUUAUACCAGUUGUCCCUGAUAAAAAAUCACUUUCUGUAUUGGUAUUUUUUCUCCUGAAUUUAAUAAAUUCCACAUUAGUGGUAAUAAGUUGAGGCUAGAACAUGUGUCCUAUUAUAAAUGAACAAUUGGAUAUCAUUAGGUUGUCCCCCCUAUCCUUUGUACAUAUAUCUUUAGGUGUGUUAAUCCAUUCAGUAGACACAUUAAUGAGCACGGGUUGAAGUGUAAUAUUGGAGGAAGUAAGGCUUGUUGACCUCAGCAAGGAGUUUAAUACCUCUAAUUAAAUUAGAUAGUCGACAGUCAGUAUAAAGAAAUAGCCAUGCCUCUGGCAAGCUAGAAUUAUUUAUGACUCUGGUCCUUUGCUUUAAACUUGGUAGGGUAAAAUCAUUUAUAUCCAUUUUAUAGAAACUAAUUUUAGUUCUGAUUUUUUAUUUAAAAUAUGUGAUUUGUAAAUUAUUUUCAAACAUUUUAUUUUCUCAGAAUGAGAAGUAAAUAUCCUUGGACCUAUUUAAAUGUAGCAUUUAUAUUUCUUGUGAAGAGAAGCUUUUUCAAGGCUCAAGACAGUAGCAGCAGAAUAUUUACAACAUAGACUAUACUUCUUGAGCAAAUUAGCCAAACAUUCAGUUUAGCUAAGUUUCUCUUAGAAAUGUUGCACCACCAUAUAAAAAUCCUGAUAUAACCCCAGUCCAAGCAAUCUGUUCUAUAAAUUAUCUCUUCCUGAGGAAGAUUGAUGGAAAAUGGUUAAAAAUAAUUUCCACUUAACUGAGUGUAUUCACCCCUAAAAAUCAAAAGUGCUGCAAGCAUUGGUAUAAAGUGUUCAUAGGAGCCUCUCUCAUUUCCUCUGUCUCCUUGUUCUAGCCACUUGCUGAUACUCUGCUUCAUAGGUAGCUGAAUCAUCCUUUUAGAAGUUUGAUGAAGAUCAAGUUGAGAUAAUUGUAACAUACUUAGUUGAACUCUCUAGUCUAUGUUUCAUUUCCUGGACCCCCCAAAAUAGGGGGAAAGAAGCACUUUAUUUAAGUCCAUUUCCUCUGAAAUACUAUUAGUGUAAUGGAAAGUGUUUCAUUUUCUGUCUUGAAAUUUACUCACAAUAGUUGUGCAAAUAAAUGAACCUUGUAGUGCUGCUUGGUCUGAUUUUUUAUUUUAAAUCUGUUUUUCUUUAUUUUAUACAGAAAUAUAAGAUACUUUCCAAAGAACUAUAUGCUAAAUAUAGUCUGAAAAAUGAAUUUGUUAAAAAAUAAAUUUAAGGAAUAAUUUUUAAAUUUUUUCAUUAUUUUAGUAAAAGUGAAGUUAGGAUUAUAGUUAAUAAGUGCUGUGAAAUUAUACUCAUUGUUUGAGUCCUAAAUAUAACAAUCUUAUAGAAGAAACUCUGCCCAUAACUCCAGUUUUUACAUAUAUACUCCUGAUGACAAGAAUAGAGGAUUGAGAAAACAGAAAAUAUAAAUGGUUCAAUGCAAGUUUAUCUUACCACAGUAAAUGUUAUGUGGGUGAGAUAGCAGAGGCCUCUCAUUGUAUAGGGAAUAAAAUUCUUUUUUUUUUUUUUUUGAGACGGAGUCUCACUAUGUUGCCACACUGGAGUGCAAUGGCGCGAUCUCUUUUCACUGCAACCUCCACCUCCUGGGUUCAAGCGAUUCUCCUGACUCAGCCUCCCGAGUAGCUGGGACUACAGGCGUGCACCACCUUUUAGUAGAGACAAGGUUUCACCAUGUUUGCCAGGAUGGUCUCGAUCUCUUGACCUCAUGAUCUGCCCGCCUCAGCCUCCCAAAGUGCUGGGAUCACAGGCGUGAGCCACUGUGCCCGGCCGGGAAUAAAAUUCUAAUUCCUCACUAUGGCACUACGUGAUUUGGCCCCACCAGCCUGCCUACCUCUAGAUCUCAUCUCCUGUCUUUUUCCUUUUCAUUUACCAUAAUCUGGCCUCACUGACUGACAUUCUGACCUUCCAACAUGUCAAACUCAUUCACAUCUUAAGGGCUGUGUACACUUACUACUCUCUCAGUUUGAAAUGUUUUUUCUCCACAUUAUCAGGCUUCCUCAUUCUAAUUCUUCUGUUCUUAAACUCACAUGACAGUUUCUCAGAAAGACCUUUUUAGACCAUCCUAGCUAAAUAAGCCCCUUUCUACUCAGGAACUUUAUCACAUUACCCUAUAUUAUUUUCUUUAUAGAUUUAUCAGCAUGUAAGUUUACCUUGUUUAUUUUUGUAUAUGUUUAUCUGACUCCUCCCACUAGAAUAUCAAGGUCAUGAGAACAAGGACUUUGUCUCUUUUGCUUACUGCUGUAUCUCCAGCACCUAGUACCAGGCCUGUUGGCAUUUAACAAAUGUUUUUUCAGUGAAUUACCACAGCUACCAUAGCCACAAAUCAAAAGAACUAUCUAUAGACACCUUUGUCUUUAUCAAAGUGACAUAUUUAAAUAAAUGCCAUAACUGCAGAUAAUUCUAUUUUUAUGCUAUGUACUGGGUAAUGAUAGGAAAAAAAUGCAAGAUAAGUAUUGUUAUAUUAUCUUUUUAAUAGUCACCAGUAUUUAUUGAAUGCCCACUCUGCUAAGGCAUAGUAUUGGAUGCUGUGCCUGUUGUUUUCAAGAAACUUUUCCUGAUUGCUAAAAAUGAAUAAUCUAAACAGCAAGUGAAUGUAGGAAAAUAUGUGUGACUAUUAGAAGGUAUAUUAAAGCAUGUUUUCUCACAUGAUUGAGGGUUAUAUCAUAGAGUGUUUUUUACUAAGUGUGAGUGCCUGAAAGAUGGGGGAAAGAAUGGGAACUUGGGGCAGUAAGAAUACUAAGUUACAGUUUCUACACGUAUACCCCUAUCUCCUGAAGUAAUUGCGUAACCUAAUUAACUUCUGUGUGUUCUUCAGCUUUUAGUUCAAGAGCUAUUAUAGAUCCAUGUCCUUUGUUAUUUGUAUUGAGAAAAGUAUAUUUAGAGCAUCAUUUGUAUUUUUAAAUUAUUUAUUUAUUUAUUGUAUGGUUAUUUUACUCUGUCUCCUCCACUGUACACAAAGCUUUGCUAGCAGAGACCAUGUCUGUUUUUACUCAUUGUUGCAUCUGCAAAAGCUAGCAUUUGGUCAGCUCUCAAUAUUUGGUUAUGAAUGAAAGAAGGUGGAUAUGGAGGAGGGAAGGAAGAGAAAAAAGACUUUUAAGACCUCAUGAAUUAGUAUGUGUGGUAUGUAGGAUGAGUAGCAUGUGAUCUAGGACAGCAGUAGAGGAAUAGGAAGGAAAGUACAGAAAAGGAAUAUACUUUUUUAAAAAAAUGAAGAGCUCAUUAGCAAUGUAGUAAGGAAAACAGAGUAAUCAAAAAAGACUAAAAGACAAUCAGGUUUUAAUCCUGAGUGAUUAUAAUUAGUUGUUAGGUACUUUUAACAGAAAUGGAGAAGUCAGGAAGAUAAAUUGAUUUAGUGAGAGACAUAAUACAGUUACUUUAUAAGAAUUCUAGUCUCCAGCCCCAGAUAAGUGAUAUUAUAUGGCACUGAGGAAAUCUAGAAUUGACUCUGGAAUUCCUGUUGGUAAUCAUGGAGAAUGAGUGCAUUGCCAUAAGAUGAAUGUCUUAGUCCAUUCAGGCUGAUAUAACAAAAAUACCAUAGACUGAAUGGCUUAUAAACCACAGAAAUUUAUUUCUCACAGUUCUGGGGGCUGAGAAAUCUAAGAUCAAGAUGCUGACAGAUUCAUUGUCUGAUGAGGGACCACUCCCUUGUUCACAGAUGACCAUCUUCUCAUUGUAACCUUAUAUAUAAUAGCAGAAGAGUCAAGUAAGCUCUCUGGGGUCUCUUUUAUAAGGACAUUAAUCCCUUAUAAAGGAGCCCGCAUAACAUAAUCACCUCCCAGAGUUCCCUACCUUCCGAUACCAACACACUGGGGGGUUAGGAUUUCACAAUAUGAAUUUGGGGGGUGGAUGGGAUGCAAACAUUCAGUCUGUAGCAAUGGGUGAACAUCUGAUUUUCACAGAAGAACAUGGAGCAGGCCAUAGACUAUAGAAAUUAACCAACAUUCGUGAGCUUCAUGUCAGUGCCUGGCAAAAUAGGAUUAUUAAACAGAUGGUUUGUGAGCACUUAGAUAAUGAAGUGUAGUGAUCACUAGGAGCCACCAUGAGUUCACCAUAACAAAUCACAUCAAAAUAACUUAAUUUGUUUUAAUAGGAUUACUAGAUUAGGGAAAACCAUAGACUGCAAUAAAGCAUUUAACUAAGUUGCUUGUUGUGGACAAGUUGAAGAAAUGUGGUCUUAAUAAGAGUUUGAUAAGUAUAUUCAUGAGUGAUUGUAUAAUCAUAUUCAUAGCACAUAAAUUAAUUAUUUAACAAGAAACAAUAUAGGGAGGUGGUUACAGUAUAGGUUCUAGAACCAGCCUGCCUUGGUUUGAAUCCUGGCUCUGCCACUUACUAUUUGUAUGACCUUAGGCGAGUUACUUCAUCCUUUUAAGCUUCAAUUCCUCUCCUGUAAAAAUAGGGAUAAUAAUAAUUAUUACUACUUCAUAGUGUUGUUGUGGAAAUUUAAUGAAUUGUCACAAACAGUAAGCAGUAAGCACUUAAUAAAUACCUUUAAUAAAUAUAGGGUUUUGUGGAUUUUUUUAACCAGGAGGAAAGUCUGUAAUGACUUGCUGUAAGGCUCUUAACCAAGCCUGUCCCAUUUGACAUUUUUGUCCAAAAUGUAAAUGAAGACACUGGAAUUUGAACUUAAGGAUAGCCCAAAUCUGGCAGAGAGCCAGCACAUGAAUAGCAUAGUCAGGCUAACAAUAGACCUUCAUAAGCUUAAAGAUAAUCUGAACCUGGCAAGGGAAAAUUAUGAAAUCCCUUCUUUAGUUCUAGCAGUCAAUUGUACCUGCUUAAAAGAACUUUGUAAGAAAAAGACUUAGCAACUUGAACUGACUACAAGUUCCAUUUGAGCCAUCAUUUUUAAAAUGCAGAAAGUAAUUUAUUGAACAGACUGAAGGAAGAAACAGCCCCACUGUGGGUUUGCUGUAUUAUCCAGAGCAUGUGUUGAUACUGUAAUUCUAUUCCAUACACAAGUUUAAUAGAAAUAUUAGUAAACUGAGACAAUAACCCAAGAUAAUGAAUAUGUUUGUAAACUGUAAGAGGAGCUAAGAAGAACACUUUUAACCUGGAAAAGGAAAGGUAAGAUAUAUAUUAGACUGAUCUUCAGAUAACAGAAAAUAUAUAGAAUACAGAUUGGAUUUAUUUGGUAAGGCUCAUUUUGGAAGAGCUAGCAUCCAGAAGGCAGUUUUUAGCUUAGUAUUAAGAUGUUCUAAUGAUUGUAGCUCUUUAAAAAUGAAAUGGGGGCCAGGC